ACACGCACGCCGCCUCUGUUUGUACACAGUGCGCUCCCGGCGGCCCGCUCGCUCCCCUCCAGCUCACGCUUCAUUGUUCUCCAAGUCAGAAGCCCCGCAGCCGCCGCGCGGAGAACAGCGACAGCCGAGCGCCCGGUCCGCCUGUCUGCCGGUGGGUCUGCCUGCCCGCGCAGCAGACCCGGGGCGGCCGCGGGAGCCCGCGCCCCGCCCGCCGCGCCUCUGCCGGGACCCACCCGCAGCGGAGGGCUGAGCCCGCCGGCGGCUCCCCGGAGCUCACCCACCUCCGCGCGCCGGAGCGCAGGCAAAAGGGGAGGAAAGGCUCCUCUCUUUAGUCACCACUCUCGCCCUCUCCAAGAAUUUGUUUAACAAAGCGCUGAGGAAAGAGAACGUCUUCUUGAAUUCUUUAGUAGGGGCGGAGUCUGCUGCUGCCCUGCGCUGCCACCUCGGCUACACUGCCCUCCGCGACGACCCCUGACCAGCCGGGGUCACGUCCGGGAGACGGGAUCAUGAAGCGCUCGGUAGCCGUCUGGCUCUUGGUCGGGCUCAGCCUCGGUGUCCCCCAGUUCGGCAAAGGUGAUAUUUGUGAUCCCAAUCCAUGUGAAAAUGGAGGUAUCUGUUUGCCAGGAUUGGCUGAUGGUUCCUUUUCCUGUGAGUGUCCAGAUGGCUUCACAGACCCCAACUGUUCUAGUGUUGUGGAGGUUGCAUCAGAUGAAGAAGAACCAACUUCAGCAGGUCCCUGCACUCCUAAUCCAUGCCAUAAUGGAGGAACCUGUGAAAUAAGUGAAGCAUACCGAGGGGAUACAUUCAUAGGCUAUGUUUGUAAAUGUCCCCGAGGAUUUAAUGGGAUUCACUGUCAGCACAACAUAAAUGAAUGCGAAGUUGAGCCUUGCAAAAAUGGUGGAAUAUGUACAGAUCUUGUUGCUAACUAUUCCUGUGAGUGCCCAGGCGAAUUUAUGGGAAGAAAUUGUCAAUACAAAUGCUCAGGCCCACUGGGAAUUGAAGGUGGAAUUAUAUCAAACCAGCAAAUCACAGCUUCCUCUACUCACCGAGCUCUUUUUGGACUCCAAAAAUGGUAUCCCUACUAUGCACGUCUUAAUAAGAAGGGGCUUAUAAAUGCGUGGACAGCUGCAGAAAAUGACAGAUGGCCGUGGAUUCAGAUAAAUUUGCAAAGGAAAAUGAGAGUUACUGGUGUGAUUACCCAAGGAGCCAAGAGGAUUGGAAGCCCAGAGUAUAUAAAAUCCUACAAAAUUGCCUACAGUAAUGAUGGAAAGACUUGGGCAAUGUACAAAGUGAAAGGCACCAAUGAAGACAUGGUGUUUCGUGGAAACAUUGAUAACAACACUCCAUAUGCUAACUCUUUCACACCCCCCAUAAAAGCUCAGUAUGUAAGACUCUAUCCCCAAGUUUGUCGAAGACAUUGCACUUUGCGAAUGGAACUUCUUGGCUGUGAACUGUCGGGUUGUUCUGAGCCUCUGGGUAUGAAAUCAGGACAUAUACAAGACUAUCAGAUCACUGCCUCCAGCAUCUUCAGAACGCUCAACAUGGACAUGUUCACUUGGGAACCAAGGAAAGCUCGGCUGGACAAGCAAGGCAAAGUGAAUGCCUGGACCUCUGGCCACAAUGACCAGUCACAAUGGUUACAGGUGGAUCUUCUUGUUCCAACCAAAGUGACUGGCAUCAUUACACAAGGAGCUAAAGAUUUUGGUCAUGUACAGUUUGUUGGCUCCUACAAACUGGCUUACAGCAAUGAUGGAGAACACUGGACUGUAUACCAGGAUGAAAAGCAAAGAAAAGAUAAGGUUUUCCAGGGAAAUUUUGACAAUGACACUCACAGAAAAAAUGUCAUCGACCCUCCCAUCUAUGCACGACACAUAAGAAUCCUUCCUUGGUCCUGGUACGGGAGGAUCACAUUGCGGUCAGAGCUGCUGGGCUGCACAGAGGAGGAAUGAGGGGAGGCUACAUUUCACAACCCUCUUCCCUAUUUCCCUAAAAGUAUCUCCAUGGAAUGAACUGUGCAAAAUCUGUAGGAAACUGAAUGGUUUUUUUUUUUUUUUCAUGAAAAAGUGCUCAAAUUAUGGUAGGCAACUAACGGUGUUUUUAAGGGGGUCUAAGCCUGCCUUUUCAAUGAUUUAAUUUGAUUUUAUUUUAUCCGUCAAAUCUCUUAAGUAACAACACAUUAAGUGUGAAUUACUUUUCUCUCAUUGUUUCCUGAAUUAUUCGCAUUGGUAGAAAUAUAUUAGGGAAAGAAAGUAGCCUUCUUUUUAUAGCAAGAGUAAAAAAGUCUCAAAGUCAUCAAAUAAGAGCAAGAGUUGAUAGAGCUUUUACAAUCAAUACUCACCUAAUUCUGAUAAAAGGAAUACUGCAAUGUUAGCAAUAAGUUUUUUUCUUCUGUAAUGACUCUACGUUAUCCUGUUUCCCUGUGCCUACCAAACACUGUCAAUGUUUAUUACAAAAUUUUAAAGAAGAAUAUGUAACAUGCAGUACUGAUAUUAUAAUUCUCAUUUUACUUUCAUUAUUUCUAAUAAGAGAUUAUGUGACUUCUUUUUCUUUUAGUUCUAUUCUACAUUCUUAAUAUUGUAUAUUACCUGAAUAAUUCAAUUUUUUUCUAAUUGAAUUUCCUAUUAGUUGACUAAAAGAAGUGUCAUGUUUACUCAUAUAUGUAGAACAUGACUGCCUAUCAGUAGAUUGAUCUGUAUUUAAUAUUCGUUAAUUAAAUCUGCAGUUUUAUUUUUGAAGGAAGCCAUAACUAUUUAAUUUCCAAAUAAUUGCUUCAUAAAGAAUCCCAUACUCUCAGUUUGCACAAAAGAACAAAAAAUAUAUAUGUCUCUUUAAAUUUAAAUCUUCAUUUAGAUGGUAAUUACAUAUCCUUAUAUUUACUUUAAAAAAUCGGCUUAUUUGUUUAUUUUAUAAAAAAUUUAGCAAAGAAAUAUUAAUAUAGUGCUGCAUAGUUUGGCCAAGCAUACUCAUCAUUUCUUUGUUCAGCUCCACAUUUCCUGUGAAACUAACAUCUUAUUGAGAUUUGAAACUGGUGGUAGUUUCCCAGGAAGGCACAGGUGGAGUUAUUUGUGAGAAGCAAAGUGUUUACUAAUGACAAAGUAGUAAACCAUUUUCAAGAUGAAAACUGAUUUCUAUUUAUUUUGCUUCAAAGGUCCUGAAAAAAUAAGCAAUUAUCAUAACAAUUUGUUAUUGAUACUGGAGGUUUCAUUGACAUGUCUCUCAAAUUAAAGCUCACACUGCCUCCAUAAAAGUCUUCAACAUCUAAUUUAUAAGCUUUACAAGUAUUUAUUUUAUAAGGCUUAGACAGAAUUAUUGGAGUUUUAAAUUAAGUGUAUUGGAAAAGAAAGGAUGGUAUGUGUAUGAAAUGUUAAGAUCCUACGCAACACUGCUAUUUUUUUCCUUUAAUAUUUGUGCUGCAUAACAAAAGCCACUAGACUGUUACUGUCUUGUCUGUCCAUGUGUUAACAGCAUUUCUUAAUGAUGUAUAUAUGGAGUGGUCUUCAAUCAUAGUGAAGAAUUUAAAGAGAAAGUCAAUUGUAUUGGCAUUUUUAAUAAGAACAAAAUUAGUUCGUCUAAGGGGACUGGCUGGCCACAUAUUUGUUCCUUGCCCAUAUGCUUUCUACUUCUUGUUCUUAUUAUGAAAUUAUGAAUUUGAAGCCUCUGAAAUGGUGAUCAGUUUUCAACAUCUUUCAAAAACAAAAUUACUAUUUCCUCCAUAUUGCCUUUUUUAGAUAACUUUAAAGUUAGGAUUUUAAAAUAUUUGUAACUGGCUAAAUUUUAAAGUCGUGACAAAUAAUUACUUAGGUUCAGAAAUAUACACACACUUACUCUUUAGCCAGUUUCUUUCAAGGUUUACUGUCCCAUCAGAUAUCUAGCCAUUUUCCUUUGCAAAUUACAUACCUUCUUAAGAGUGUAUUUUUAAGAUUAUUACUUACGCUUUAUGAUGAUAUAGUUUUUCAAAAUUAUUUAUAGCUUCAUAUGAUGUUUUGUAAUUUUUUCUAUUGAUACCUGUUUUAAAAAUAUUUUCCAAGGAAGUUGAUUAAAAUUAUAUUUGUUACCUUUUAGAAAAAGCAUUGAAAUGAGUUUCUCUUGCUUUUUCAUUUUCCCUCUGCUUUAUAUGCUCUUCGCAAUACAUCAUGUCCAACGGGAUACCUAUUGUUCUCAUGACACCCAAAAUUGAUGAGAGCAAAGGGGUCGCACCAUAUGGAAAUGUUGAAAACUAUUGUAAAGUAGUAUUAUGAAGUAGCUUUUGUGUCAUUCAUGUCGAUGACAUGAAAGUGAAGUAAAUUUAUUCUAUGUAAAUUCACACUAAAACCAGUACAGUACCAUAAGUAGAAUACAUGUAAGAAUCACCUAGUCUUCACUAUAUUGAGUAAAUAUAACAUGCUAAUUUUACAAUUAAUGAAACUAAACUUUUAAACAUCUCCAUUAUAUCUACAUCCUUUUGAAGGUAUUUAUCAUAGUUGCCAAUUUUAAUUUUAGGAUUGACUUUCUCUUUCUGAAUGACUUCAUAAAGUUUGGUGUGAAUUUUGAAGACUUGGGUUACUAAUGAUUGUAUCUUUGCUAGUCAACAACUUAUGAAAUAUACUCAAUGCGUCUGAUGUGUCAUUAAGUGCAGAAAUAACUAAGACACAAAUAACCUUUGCAAACCUUCAAGCUGUGUAAUAUUCCAAUGUUGUUUUUUUCUUUGUAUAUAUACUUAUAUCACGUAGGAUGUAAAACCAGUAUGACCUUGUCUAGUCUCCAAACUUAAAAUAAACUUUUGAAAAGCUGGGAUUCUUUUGAAGCAGUUGUAAUUAAACACAUUUAUAAGAAUA